AGCCAGUCCUGAGCACCUAACCAUGUUGGGCAUCACUGUCCUCGCUGCGCUCUUGGCCUGUGCCUCCAGCUGUGGGGUGCCCAGCUUCCCGCCCAACCUAUCCGCCCGAGUGGUGGGAGGAGAGGAUGCCCGGCCCCACAGCUGGCCCUGGCAGAUCUCCCUCCAGUACCUCAAGAACGACACGUGGAGGCAUACGUGUGGCGGGACUUUGAUUGCUAGCAACUUCGUCCUCACUGCCGCCCACUGCAUCAGCAACACCCGGACCUACCGUGUGGCCGUGGGAAAGAACAACCUGGAGGUGGAAGACGAAGAAGGAUCCCUGUUUGUGGGUGUGGACACCAUCCACGUCCACAAGAGAUGGAAUGCCCUCCUGUUGCGCAAUGAUAUUGCCCUCAUCAAGCUUGCAGAGCAUGUGGAGCUGAGUGACACCAUCCAGGUGGCCUGCCUGCCAGAGAAGGACUCCCUGCUCCCCAAGGACUACCCCUGCUAUGUCACCGGCUGGGGCCGCCUCUGGACCAACGGCCCCAUUGCUGAUAAGCUGCAGCAGGGCCUGCAGCCCGUGGUGGAUCACGCCACGUGCUCCAGGAUUGACUGGUGGGGCUUCAGGGUGAAGAAAACCAUGGUGUGCGCUGGGGGCGAUGGCGUCAUCUCAGCCUGCAAUGGGGACUCCGGUGGCCCACUGAACUGCCAGUUGGAGAACGGUUCCUGGGAGGUGUUUGGCAUCGUCAGCUUUGGCUCCCGGCGGGGCUGCAACACCCGCAAGAAGCCGGUAGUCUACACCCGGGUGUCCGCCUACAUCGACUGGAUCAACGAGAAAAUGCAGCUGUGAUUUGUUGCUGGGAGCGGCGGCAGCGAGUCCCUGCAACAGCAAUAAACUUCCUUCUCCUCGGGCCACCUGGAUCCUUGAUUUGUGCAGCUUCUGUUGCUUCCCUCCUCUCUGGUGCUGCCCCUUUCCACACUAUGGAGCCAAAGAGAGACCCCACUCAGCCAGUUUCCCCCACCCUGCAUUAGACAGGUGGGGAAACAGAGGCCGGGAGAGAGGGCCAAGGAAGGAGCCUCCUGGGGCAUUAAUGGGAGGCAGGGGGCUGGGGUGGAGAGCCCAGGGAGUCCUGCGUGAAGCCGGAGGGGAUGGGAGUGAAGGACGCAUCAGACACCUUCCCCGCUCCAUCUCACAAGCUGCGAACAGGUGAGACCCUGAUGAAAUCACUCGCUUCUCCGAUCCUACCUCCACCGAGGGGCCUGGCAGGUCCUCACAGCCCCCCAGCAGCAGGUGGAAGACAGGGUCUCCCCAAAAGCAGCGUCCCCCAGGCCAGAGAGACCAGGCCACAGGAGGAUGGCCAAAGCUCAGGGACAACCACUCCUGGGGAAGGGGCUCCCUAGCAGGGACCCCCCACCCCCACCCCGCAGCACAGACCCCAUGGCUGCUGUUGGCAGGGGCUCUCUGCUUUGAGAAGUGUUUAGUGAGCCAGCCCCUGUGUCCAGUCCUGUGCUGGGCAUGAUGAGGGUACAGGAAGAGGAAGAGACCCCAGCAUCAUCCUCAGGAGACAUACGUUUGAAGAAGGCAAUGGUUUCCACACAGAAUCACAGUGGUCAGAGCUGGAUAUGCUUUCAUUGCAUUAGACAAGUGGGGAAACUGAGGCCCAGAGAGAGGAAGGAGUUGGGAUAGCUGGCAAUGCCUGAUCCAGGAGAAGAGAGUUCUCCUGAGGCUGACAAGAGGCCAAGAGGAGCCAGAGAUGAGAUAGACCCAGUGUCCAGGGAGGGACAUGCCAGUGGGAUCAGACCCUGAUGACAGGGGCAGCCAGAGAUGAGAGAGAUCCAAUGUCCAGGGAGGGACAUGCCAGGGGGAUCAGACCCUGAUGAUAGGGGCCUCUGGCCUGGCCUGCUCCUGGGAAUGUCCUGUUCUGUGGGGGUGCCCCCAGCCCAGCCUCUGGACCCCUCGCUGGAGAGCCCUCGGCUGCAGCUACCUCAGACUGGCCCAAGAGUUGUCCCUUUUCUCCACCAGACUUUGUCCCCUGGGAGUGGGGACCAUGGUGUGACUCCCACACCCCCAUGAUGCCAAGGCAAGUCUCAGGAAAGACUUGACUUACUCAACAAGCAGUGGGAGCUACAGGGAGCCCAGCACCACCCAGACCCGGGAAUCCAGGAUGGGGGUACCCCAGCUGUGCAGGAGACAGACCAGUAAAUAGAUCAUUAAAUUCCCUGGUAUACAUUUGAAAACAGAAAUACAGACCAGAAGCAUAGAAACAGGACACCUGAAGCAGUGUCAGUUGGCGGGAGGAAUCCAGGAUGGCUUCCUGGAGGUGAUGAUGCCCAAGCUUGGUCUUAAAAUUUGACUAGAAGGUACCCAAGUACAGAACGUAGUCCUUCUUAAGUUUGCUUAAUCUAAACUUCAUUCCCACCUAUCCUCUUCUUUUUUUUUUUUUUUUUUUUGAGACGGAGUCUUGCUCUGAUGCCCAGGCUGGAGUGCAGUGGCACAAUCUCAGCUCACUGCAACCUCCACCUCCCAGGUUCAAGUGAUUCUUCUGCCUCAGCCUCCCAAGUAGCUGGGAUUACAGGCACGCACCACCAUGCACAGCUAAUUUUUUUUUUUUUUUUUUAGACAGAGUCUCGCUCUCUCACCUGGGCUGUAGUGCAGUGGUGCCAUCUCGGCUCACUGCAAGCUCCGCCUCCCAGGUUCACGCCAUUCUCCUGCCUCAGCCUCCUGAGUAGCUGGGACUACAGGCGCCAGCCACCAUGCCUGGCUAAUUUUUUUUUUUUUUGUAUUUUUAGCAGAGACGGGGUUUCACCGUGUUAGCCAGGAUGGUCUCGAUCUCCUGAUCUCGUGAUCCACCUGCCUCGGCCUCCCAAAGUGCUGGCAUUACAGGCGUGAGCCACCGUGCCCGGCCCCAGCUAAUUUUUUUGUAUUUUUUUAGUAGAGAUGGGGUUUCACCAUGUCGUCCAGGCUGGUCUCAAACUCCUGACCUCAGGUGAUCUGCCCGCCUUGGCCUCCCAAAGUACUGGGAUCACAGGUGUGAGCCACCACACCCGGUCUCAUUCCCAGCUAUCUUCUUUUGUGUAUGUCUUUAUAUUGGGGGUUAUAAAUGCUAAAUGCUUGCUGUCCUCAGAUCCCUUGUAGUUAGGGAGCUAAUUAAAAUGUUAAUUAAUAUUACAAUGUUAUUUAAGCAAUGUUAAAUAAUAUCUAACAUUUAUUGGGCACUUAGUAUGUGCCAAGCACUAUCCUAUAGGUUUUACAUUAUCUCAAUCCCCAGAAACAAUCCCAUGAGGUAGGUUACUAUUAACAUCAUGCCCAUUUUACAGAUGAGAAAACUGAGGCCAGACAGGGUUAGUGACUUCCCAAUGUGUGAACUAGAAGGUAGUGGAGCCGGAAUCCAGACUUUAGUGAUCUGACUCCAGGGCCUGUGCUCUUGUCCACCAUGCUCUGCUGCCCUGCAAUGUAAAACAUCCUCCAGAAAAAAAAUAAAUAAAUAAAAACUUCCCUGAUG